AGACGGUUACCUGGCACGCUGGCCACAUUCUGCCUCACUCUUAUCAGAGUCUGAGCUACUGGCAGUGCUUUCAGCUCUGAGUUGAGGCACCUCGAACCUUGUUUUUGUGGUGAAGGAUCCUAAAGUGCUGUGGGGAGUGAUCACAUUUUUCACAACAUCCCUGACUCCACCUCUUCUGCCACAAACGUCAGCAUGGUGGUAUCAGCCGGCCCUUGGUCCAGUGAGAAGGCAGAGAUGAACAUUCUAGAAAUCAACGAGACAUUGCGCCCCCAGCUGGCAGAGAAGAAACAGCAGUUCAGAAACCUCAAAGAGAAAUGUUUUCUAACUCAACUGGCCGGCUUCCUGGCCAACCAACAGAAGAAAUACAAGUAUGAAGAGUGUAAAGACCUCAUAAAAUUUAUGCUGAGGAAUGAGCGACAGUUCAAGGAGGAGAAGCUUGCAGAGCAGCUGAAGCAAGCUGAGGAGCUCAGGCAAUAUAAAGUCCUGGUUCACUCUCAGGAACGAGAGCUGACCCAGCUAAGGGAGAAGUUACGGGAAGGGAGAGAUGCCUCCCGCUCAUUGUAUGAGCAUCUCCAGGCCCUCCUCACUCCGUAUGAGCCGGACAAGUCCCAGGGGCAGGACCUCCAAGAACAGCUGGCUGAGGGGUGUAGACUGGCACAGCACCUUGUCCAAAAGCUCAGCCCAGAAAAUGACGAAGAUGAGGAUGAAGAUGUUCAAGUUGAGGAGGCUGAGAAAGUACUGGAAUCAUCUGCCCCCAGGGAGGUGCAGAAGGCUGAAGAGAGCAAAGUCCCUGAGGACUCACUGGAGGAAUGUGCCAUCACUUGUUCAAAUAGCCACGGCCCUUGUGACUCCAACCAGCCUCACAAGAACAUCAAAAUCACAUUUGAGGAAGACGAAGUCAACUCAACUCUGGUUGUAGACAGAGAAUCCUCUCAUGAUGAAUGUCAGGAUGCUCUAAACAUUCUCCCAGUCCCUGGCCCCACCUCUUCUGCCACAAACGUCAGCAUGGUGGUAUCAGCCGGCCCUUUGUCCAGCGAGAAGGCAGAGAUGAACAUUCUAGAAAUCAAUGAGAAAUUGCGCCCCCAGCUGGCAGAGAAGAAACAGCAGUUCAGAAACCUCAAAGAGAAAUGUUUUCUAACUCAACUGUCCGGCUUCCUGGCCAACCAACAGAAGAAAUACAAAUAUGAAGAGUGCAAAGACCUCAUAAAAUUUAUGCUGAGGAAUGAGCGACAGUUCAAGGAGGAGAAGCUUGCGGAGCAGCUGAAGCAAGCUGAGGAGCUCAGGCAAUAUAAAGUCCUGGUUCACGCUCAGGAACGAGAGCUGACCCAGUUAAGGGAGAAGUUGCGGGAAGGGAGAGAUGCCUCCCGCUCAUUGAAUGAGCAUCUCCAGGCCCUCCUCACUCCGGAUGAGCCGGACAAGUCCCAGGGGCAGGACCUCCAAGAACAGCUGGCUGAGGGGUGUAGACUGGCACAGCACCUUGUCCAAAAGCUCAGCCCAGAAAAUGACAACGAUGACGAUGAAGAUGUUCAAGUUGAGGUGGCUGAGAAAGUGCAGAAAUCGUCUGCCCCCAGGGAGAUGCAGAAGGCUGAAGAAAAGGAAGUCCCUGAGGACUCACUGGAGGAAUGUGCCAUCACUUAUUCAAAUAGCCAUGGCUCUUAUGACUCCAACCAGCCACAUAGGAAAACCAAAAUCACAUUUGAGGAAGACAAAGUCGACUCAACUCUCAUUGGCUCAUCCUCUCAUGUUGAAUGGGAGGAUGCUGUACACAUUAUUCCAGAAAAUGAAAGUGAUGAUGAGGAAGAGGAAGAAAAAGGGCCAGUGUCUCCCAGGAAUCUGCAGGAGUCUGAAGAGGAGGAAGUCCCCCAGGAGUCCUGGGAUGAAGGUUAUUCGACUCUCUCAAUUCCUCCUGAAAUGUUGGCCUCGUACCAGUCUUACAGCAGCACAUUUCACUCAUUAGAGGAACAGCAAGUCUGCAUGGCUGUUGACAUAGGCAGACAUCGGUGGGAUCAAGUGAAAAAGGAGGACCAAGAGGCAACAGGUCCCAGGCUCAGCAGGGAGCUGCUGGAUGAGAAAGGGCCUGAAGUCUUGCAGGACUCACUGGAUAGAUGUUAUUCAACUCCUUCAGGUUGUCUUGAACUGACUGACUCAUGCCAGCCCUACAGAAGUGCCUUUUAUGUAUUGGAGCAACAGCGUGUUGGCUUGGCUGUUGACAUGGAUGAAAUUGAAAAGUACCAAGAAGUGGAAGAAGACCAAGACCCAUCAUGCCCCAGGCUCAGCAGGGAGCUGCUGGAUGAGAAAGAGCCUGAAGUCUUGCAGGACUCACUGGAUAGAUGUUAUUCGACUCCUUCAGGUUAUCUUGAACUGCCUGACUUAGGCCAGCCCUACAGCAGUGCUGUUUACUCAUUGGAGGAACAGUACCUUGGCUUGGCUCUUGACGUGGACAGAAUUAAAAAGGACGAAGAAGAGGAAGAAGACCAAGACCCACCAUGCCCCAGGCUCAGCAGGGAGCUGCUGGAGGUAGUAGAGCCUGAAGUCUUGCAGGACUCACUGGAUAGAUGUUAUUCAACUCCUUCCAGUUGUCUUGAACAGCCUGACUCCUGCCAGCCCUAUGGAAGUUCCUUUUAUGCAUUGGAGGAAAAACAUGUUGGCUUUUCUCUUGACGUGGGAGAAAUUGAAAAGAAGGGGAAGGGGAAGAAAAGAAGGGGAAGAAGAUCAAAGAAGGAAAGAAGAAGGGGAAGAAAAGAAGGGGAAGAAGAUCAAAACCCACCAUGCCCCAGGCUCAGCAGGGAGCUGCUGGAUGAGAAAGAGCCUGAAGUCUUGCAGGACUCACUGGAUAGAUGUUAUUCGACUCCUUCAGGUUAUCUUGAACUGCCUGACUUAGGCCAGCCCUACAGCAGUGCUGUUUACUCAUUGGAGGAACAGUACCUUGGCUUGGCUCUUGACGUGGACAGAAUUAAAAAGGACGAAGAAGAGGAAGAAGACCAAGACCCACCAUGCCCCAGGCUCAGCAGGGAGCUGCUGGAGGUAGUAGAGCCUGAAGUCUUGCAGGACUCACUGGAUAGAUGUUAUUCAACUCCUUCCAGUUGUCUUGAACAGCCUGACUCCUGCCAGCCCUAUGGAAGUUCCUUUUAUGCAUUGGAGGAAAAACAUGUUGGCUUUUCUCUUGACGUGGGAGAAAUUGAAAAGAAGGGGAAGGGGAAGAAAAGAAGGGGAAGAAGAUCAAAGAAGGAAAGAAGAAGGGGAAGAAAAGAAGGGGAAGAAGAUCAAAACCCACCAUGCCCCAGGCUCAGCAGGGAGCUGCUGGAUGAGAAAGGGCCUGAAGUCUUGCAGGACUCACUGGAUAGAUGUUAUUCAACUCCUUCAGGUUGUCUUGAACUGACUGACUCAUGCCAGCCCUACAGAAGUGCCUUUUAUGUAUUGGAGCAACAGCGUGUUGGCUUGGCUGUUGACAUGGAUGAAAUUGAAAAGUACCAAGAAGUGGAAGAAGACCAAGACCCAUCAUGCCCCAGGCUCAGCAGGGAGCUGCUGGAUGAGAAAGAGCCUGAAGUCUUGCAGGACUCACUGGAUAGAUGUUAUUCGACUCCUUCAGGUUAUCUUGAACUGCCUGACUUAGGCCAGCCCUACAGCAGUGCUGUUUACUCAUUGGAGGAACAGUACCUUGGCUUGGCUCUUGACGUGGACAGAAUUAAAAAGGACGAAGAAGAGGAAGAAGACCAAGACCCACCAUGCCCCAGGCUCAGCAGGGAGCUGCUGGAGGUAGUAGAGCCUGAAGUCUUGCAGGACUCACUGGAUAGAUGUUAUUCAACUCCUUCCAGUUGUCUUGAACAGCCUGACUCCUGCCAGCCCUAUGGAAGUUCCUUUUAUGCAUUGGAGGAAAAACAUGUUGGCUUUUCUCUUGACGUGGGAGAAAUUGAAAAGAAGGGGAAGGGGAAGAAAAGAAGGGGAAGAAGAUCAAAGAAGGAAAGAAGAAGGGGAAGAAAAGAAGGGGAAGAAGAUCAAAACCCACCAUGCCCCAGGCUCAGCAGGGAGCUGCUGGAUGAGAAAGGGCCUGAAGUCUUGCAGGACUCACUGGAUAGAUGUUAUUCAACUCCUUCAGGUUGUCUUGAACUGACUGACUCAUGCCAGCCCUACAGAAGUGCCUUUUAUGUAUUGGAGCAACAGCGUGUUGGCUUGGCUGUUGACAUGGAUGAAAUUGAAAAGUACCAAGAAGUGGAAGAAGACCAAGACCCAUCAUGCCCCAGGCUCAGCAGGGAGCUGCUGGAUGAGAAAGAGCCUGAAGUCUUGCAGGACUCACUGGAUAGAUGUUAUUCGACUCCUUCAGGUUAUCUUGAACUGCCUGACUUAGGCCAGCCCUACAGCAGUGCUGUUUACUCAUUGGAGGAACAGUACCUUGGCUUGGCUCUUGACGUGGACAGAAUUAAAAAGGACGAAGAAGAGGAAGAAGACCAAGACCCACCAUGCCCCAGGCUCAGCAGGGAGCUGCUGGAGGUAGUAGAGCCUGAAGUCUUGCAGGACUCACUGGAUAGAUGUUAUUCAACUCCUUCCAGUUGUCUUGAACAGCCUGACUCCUGCCAGCCCUAUGGAAGUUCCUUUUAUGCAUUGGAGGAAAAACAUGUUGGCUUUUCUCUUGACGUGGGAGAAAUUGAAAAGAAGGGGAAGGGGAAGAAAAGAAGGGGAAGAAGAUCAAAGAAGGAAAGAAGAAGGGGAAGAAAAGAAGGGGAAGAAGAUCAAAACCCACCAUGCCCCAGGCUCAGCAGGGAGCUGCUGCAUGAGAAAGGGCCUGAAGUCUUGCAGGACUCACUGGAUAGAUGUUAUUCAACUCCUUCAGGUUGUCUUGAACUGACUGACUCAUGCCAGCCCUAUAGAAGUGCCUUUUACAUAUUGGAGCAGCAGCGUGUUGGCUUGGCUGUUGACAUGGAUGAAAUUGAAAAGUACAAAGAAGUGGAAGAAGACCAAGACCCAUCAUGCCCCAGGCUCAGCAGGGAGCUGCUGGAUGAGAAAGAGCCUGAAGUCUUGCAGGACUCACUGGAUAGAUGUUAUUCGACUCCUUCAGGUUAUCUUGAACUGCCUGACUUAGGCCAGCCCUACAGCAGUGCUGUUUACUCAUUGGAGGAACAGUACCUUGGCUUGGCUCUUGACGUGGACAGAUUUAAAAAGGACGAAGAAGAGGAAGAAGACCAAGACCCACCAUGCCCCAGGCUCAGCAGGGAGCUGCUGGAGGUAGUAGAGCCUGAAGUCUUGCAGGACUCACUGGAUAGAUGUUAUUCAACUCCUUCCAGUUGUCUUGAACAGCCUGACUCCUGCCAGCCCUAUGGAAGUUCCUUUUAUGCAUUGGAGGAAAAACAUGUUGGCUUUUCUCUUGAUGUGGGAGAAAUUGAAAAGAAGGGGAAGGGGAAGAAAAGAAGGGGAAGAAGAUCAAAGAAGGAAAGAAGAAGGGGAAGAAAAGAAGGGGAAGAAGAUCAAAACCCACCAUGCCCCAGGCUCAGCAGGGAGCUGCUGGAUGAGAAAGGGCCUGAAGUCUUGCAGGACUCACUGGAUAGAUGUUAUUCAACUCCUUCAGGUUGUCUUGAACUGACUGACUCAUGCCAGCCCUACAGAAGUGCCUUUUAUGUAUUGGAGCAACAGCGUGUUGGCUUGGCUGUUGACAUGGAUGAAAUUGAAAAGUACAAAGAAGUGGAAGAAGACCAAGACCCAUCAUGCCCCAGGCUCAGCAGGGAGCUGCUGGAUGAGAAAGAGCCUGAAGUCUUGCAGGACUCACUGGAUAGAUGUUAUUCGACUCCUUCAGGUUAUCUUGAACUGCCUGACUUAGGCCAGCCCUACAGCAGUGCUGUUUACUCAUUGGAGGAACAGUACCUUGGCUUGGCUCUUGACGUGGACAGAAUUAAAAAGGACCAAGAAGAGGAAGAAGACCAAGGCCCACCAUGCCCCAGGCUCAGCAGGGAGCUGCUGGAGGUAGUAGAGCCUGAAGUCUUGCAGGACUCACUGGAUAGAUGUUAUUCAACUCCUUCCAGUUGUCUUGAACAGCCUGACUCCUGCCAGCCCUAUGGAAGUUCCUUUUAUGCAUUGGAGGAAAAACAUGUUGGCUUUUCUCUUGACGUGGGAGAAAUUGAAAAGAAGGGGAAGGGGAAGAAAAGAAGGGGAAGAAGAUCAAAGAAGGAAAGAAGAAGGGGAAGAAAAGAAGGGGAAGAAGAUCAAAACCCACCAUGCCCCAGGCUCAGCAGGGAGCUGCUGGAUGAGAAAGGGCCUGAAGUCUUGCAGGACUCACUGGAUAGAUGUUAUUCAACUCCUUCAGGUUGUCUUGAACUGACUGACUCAUGCCAGCCCUACAGAAGUGCCUUUUAUGUAUUGGAGCAACAGCGUGUUGGCUUGGCUGUUGACAUGGAUGAAAUUGAAAAGUACAAAGAAGUGGAAGAAGACCAAGACCCAUCAUGCCCCAGGCUCAGCAGGGAGCUGCUGGAUGAGAAAGAGCCUGAAGUCUUGCAGGACUCACUGGAUAGAUGUUAUUCGACUCCUUCAGGUUAUCUUGAACUGCCUGACUUAGGCCAGCCCUACAGCAGUGCUGUUUACUCAUUGGAGGAACAGUACCUUGGCUUGGCUCUUGACGUGGACAGAAUUAAAAAGGACCAAGAAGAGGAAGAAGACCAAGGCCCACCAUGCCCCAGGCUCAGCAGGGAGCUGCUGGAGGUAGUAGAGCCUGAAGUCUUGCAGGACUCACUGGAUAGAUGUUAUUCAACUCCUUCCAGUUGUCUUGAACAGCCUGACUCCUGCCAGCCCUAUGGAAGUUCCUUUUAUGCAUUGGAGGAAAAACAUGUUGGCUUUUCUCUUGACGUGGGAGAAAUUGAAAAGAAGGGGAAGGGGAAGAAAAGAAGGGGAAGAAGAUCAAAGAAGGAAAGAAGAAGGGGAAGAAAAGAAGGGGAAGAAGAUCAAAACCCACCAUGCCCCAGGCUCAGCAGGGAGCUGCUGGAUGAGAAAGGGCCUGAAGUCUUGCAGGACUCACUGGAUAGAUGUUAUUCAACUCCUUCAGGUUGUCUUGAACUGACUGACUCAUGCCAGCCCUACAGAAGUGCCUUUUAUGUAUUGGAGCAACAGCGUGUUGGCUUGGCUGUUGACAUGGAUGAAAUUGAAAAGUACAAAGAAGUGGAAGAAGACCAAGACCCAUCAUGCCCCAGGCUCAGCAGGGAGCUGCUGGAUGAGAAAGAGCCUGAAGUCUUGCAGGACUCACUGGAUAGAUGUUAUUCGACUCCUUCAGGUUAUCUUGAACUGCCUGACUUAGGCCAGCCCUACAGCAGUGCUGUUUACUCAUUGGAGGAACAGUACCUUGGCUUGGCUCUUGACGUGGACAGAAUUAAAAAGGACCAAGAAGAGGAAGAAGACCAAGGCCCACCAUGCCCCAGGCUCAGCAGGGAGCUGCUGGAGGUAGUAGAGCCUGAAGUCUUGCAGGACUCACUGGAUAGAUGUUAUUCAACUCCUUCCAGUUGUCUUGAACAGCCUGACUCCUGCCAGCCCUAUGGAAGUUCCUUUUAUGCAUUGGAGGAAAAACAUGUUGGCUUUUCUCUUGAUGUGGGAGAAAUUGAAAAGAAGGGGAAGGGGAAGAAAAGAAGGGGAAGAAGAUCAAAGAAGGAAAGAAGAAGGGGAAGAAAAGAAGGGGAAGAAGAUCAAAACCCACCAUGCCCCAGGCUCAGCAGGGAGCUGCUGGAUGAGAAAGGGCCUGAAGUCUUGCAGGACUCACUGGAUAGAUGUUAUUCAACUCCUUCAGGUUGUCUUGAACUGACUGACUCAUGCCAGCCCUACAGAAGUGCCUUUUAUGUAUUGGAGCAACAGCGUGUUGGCUUGGCUGUUGACAUGGAUGAAAUUGAAAAGUACAAAGAAGUGGAAGAAGACCAAGACCCAUCAUGCCCCAGGCUCAGCAGGGAGCUGCUGGAUGAGAAAGAGCCUGAAGUCUUGCAGGACUCACUGGAUAGAUGUUAUUCGACUCCUUCAGGUUAUCUUGAACUGCCUGACUUAGGCCAGCCCUACAGCAGUGCUGUUUACUCAUUGGAGGAACAGUACCUUGGCUUGGCUCUUGACGUGGACAGAAUUAAAAAGGACCAAGAAGAGGAAGAAGACCAAGGCCCACCAUGCCCCAGGCUCAGCAGGGAGCUCCUGGAGGUAGUAGAGCCUGAAGUCUUGCAGGACUCACUGGAUAGAUGUUAUUCAACUCCUUCCAGUUGUCUUGAACAGCCUGACUCCUGCCAGCCCUAUGGAAGUUCCUUUUAUGCAUUGGAGGAAAAACAUGUUGGCUUUUCUCUUGACGUGGGAGAAAUUGAAAAGAAGGGGAAGGGGAAGAAAAGAAGGGGAAGAAGAUCAAAGAAGGAAAGAAGAAGGGGAAGAAAAGAAGGGGAAGAAGAUCAAAACCCACCAUGCCCCAGGCUCAGCAGGGAGCUGCUGGAUGAGAAAGGGCCUGAAGUCUUGCAGGACUCACUGGAUAGAUGUUAUUCAACUCCUUCAGGUUGUCUUGAACUGACUGACUCAUGCCAGCCCUACAGAAGUGCCUUUUAUGUAUUGGAGCAACAGCGUGUUGGCUUGGCUGUUGACAUGGAUGAAAUUGAAAAGUACCAAGAAGUGGAAGAAGACCAAGACCCAUCAUGCCCCAGGCUCAGCAGGGAGCUGCUGGAUGAGAAAGAUCCUGAAGUCUUGCAGGACUCACUGGAUAGAUGUUAUUCGACUCCUUCAGGUUAUCUUGAACUGCCUGACUUAGGCCAGCCCUACAGCAGUGCUGUUUACUCAUUGGAGGAACAGUACCUUGGCUUGGCUCUUGACGUGGACAAAAUUGAAAAGAAGGGGAAGGGGAAAAAAAGAAGGGGAAGAAGAUCAAAGAAGGAAAGAAGAAGGGGAAGAAAAGAAGGGGAAGAAGAUCAAAACCCACCAUGCCCCAGGCUCAACGGCGUGCUGAUGGAAGUGGAAGAGCGUGAAGUCUUACAGGACUCACUGGAUAGAUGUUAUUCGACUCCGUCAAUGUACUUUGAACUACCUGACUCAUUCCAGCACUACAGAAGUGUGUUUUACUCAUUUGAGGAACAGCACAUCAGCUUCGCCCUUUACGUGGACAAUAGGUUUUUUACUUUGACGGUGACAAGUCUCCACCUGGUGUUCCAGAUGGGAGUCAUAUUCCCACAAUAAGCAGCCCUUAGUAAUCCGAGAGAUGUCAUUCCUGCAGGCAGGACCUAUAGGCAAGUGAAGAUUUGAAUGAAAGUACAGUUCCAUUUGGAAGCCCAGACAUAGGAUGGGUCAGUGGGCAUGGCUCUAUUCCUAUUCUCAAACCAUGCCAGUGGAAACCUGUGCGCAGUCUGAAGACAAUGGACCCACGUUAGGUGUGACACGUUCACAUAACUGUGCAGCACAUGCCGGGAGUGAUCAGUCAGACAUUUUAAUUUGAACCACGUAUCUCUGGGUAGCUACAAAAUUCCUCAGGGAUUUCAUUUUGCAGGCAUGUCUCUGAGCUUCUAUACCUGCUCAAGGUCAUUGUCAUCUUUGUGUUUAGCUCAUCCAAAGGUGUUACCCUGGUUUCAAUGAACCUAACCUCAUUCUUUGUGUCUUCAGUGUUGGCUUGUUUUAGCUGAUCCAUCUGUAACACAGGAGGGAUCCUUGGCUGAGGAUUGUAUUUCAGAACCACCAACUGCUCUUGACAAUUGUUAACCCGCUAGACUCCUUUGGUUAGAGAAGCCACAGUCCUUCAGCCUCCAAUUGGUGUCAGUACUUAGGAAGACCACAGCUAGAUGGACAAACAGCAUUGGGAGGCCUUAGCCCUGCUCCUCUCUAUUCCAUCCUGUAGAGGUCAGGAGUCAGGAGUCGCUGGCAGGAGACAGCAUGUCACCCAGGACUCUGCCGGUGCAGAAUAUGAACAAUGCCAUGUUCUUGCAGAAAACGCUUAGCCUGAGUUUCAUAGGAGGUAAUCACCAGACAACUGCAGAAUGUAGAACACUGAGCAGGACAACUGACCUGUCUCCUUCACAUAGUCCAUAUCACCACAAAUCACACAACAAAAAGGAGAAGAGAUAUUUUGGGUUCAAAAAAAGUAAAAAGAUAAUGUAGCUGCAUUUCUUUAGUUAUUUUGAACCCCAAAUAUUUCCUCAUCUUUUUGUUGUUGUCAUGGAUGGUGGUGACAUGGACUUGUUUAUAGAAGACAGGUCAGCUGUCUGGCUCAAUGAUCUACAUUCUGAAGUUGUCUGAAAAUGUCUUCAUGAUUAAAUUCAGCCUAAACGUUUUGCCAGGAACACUGCAGAGACAAUGCUGUGAGUUUCCAACCUCAGCCCAUCUGCGGGCAGAGAAGGUCUAGUUUGUCCAUCACCAUUAUGAUAUCAGGACUGGUUACUUGGUUAAGGAGGGGUCUAGGAGAUCUGUCCCUUUUAGAGACACCUUACUUACAAUGAAGUACUUGGGAAAGUGGUUUUCAAGAGUAUAAAUAUCCUGUAUUCUAAUGAUCAUCCUCUAAACAUUUUAUCAUUUAUUAAUCCUCCCUGCCUGUGUCUAUUAUUAUAUUCAUAUCUCUACACUGCAAAUUUGGGGUCUCAAUUUUUACUGUGCCUUUGUUUUUACUAGUGUCUGCUGUUGCAAAAAGAAGACAUUCUCUGCCUGAGUUUUAAUUUUUGUCCAAAGUUAAUUUUAAUCUAUACAAUUAAAACCUUUUGCCUAUCACUCUGGACUUUUGGAUUGUUUUUUACAUUCAGUGUUAUAAUAUUUGAUUAUGGUGAUUGGUUUUGGUGGGUACUGAUGCGAAUUAAUAAAAACAUUUCAUUUCCA